AGCAAGUAAUGUGUGUGUGAGUAGUCAUUGGAUACAUACAUAACAGUGAGCAAGUUUAUCAGCUCCUGCAUGGCAGUGUUCUGAUGAUCUUUUGCUGCAAAAGAGCUACACCCCAAAUUAGUGGCUUAAAGUAAAAGCUUACUAGUGUAUAUGAUGAUUCUGUUGGUCCAGGAUUUGGAAAGGGCAUGGCAGGAGGUCUCAUCUCUGCUUCACAAUGCCGAUGAUUUAGCUGGGAGGACCCAAAAUGCUGGAAAAGCUGAUGGGUGCUGAUUCUCUCCAGCUUUUCAGAUCCAGAUAUACAUUGGGUAAAAUCUACUUCAUAGGUUUUCAAAGGAGCAUUCUUCUGAGCAAAUCUGAAAACUCUCUAAACUCUAUUGCAAAGGAGACAGAAGAAGGAAGAGAGACGGUAACAAGGAAAGAAGGAUGGAAGAGAAGGCAUGAGGACGGCUAUUUGGAAAUGGCACAGAGGCAUUUACAGAGAUCAUUAUGUCCUUGGGUCUCUUACCUUCCUCAGCCCUAUGCAGAACAUUCCAAGGUGAUUCUAAAUGGCAAUUUGCACUGUCAUUUUAAAAGAAUUUCUCAGAUAUUUGCUGGGCACUUUAUGGAAGGAGACACUGAGGCUUGAAGAAGUAAGCAGCCAUGUUGGAAAAGUCUUCAUGGCAAGAAACUAUGAGUUCCUUGCCUAUGAGGCCUCUAAGGACCGCAGGCAGCCUCUAGAACGAAUGUGGACCUGCAACUACAACCAGCAAAAAGACCAGUCAUGCAACCACAAGGAAAUAACUUCUACCAAAGCUGAAUGAGUUUGGAAGCAGAUUCUUCCCAGCCAAUCCUUCUGAUGACAAUGUAGUCUGGCCAACAUCUUCACUGGACUCUGACGGACUCUGUGUCUGGGACCCAGCUGAUAACACGUGGUGAUGGGAUUGUAUUUGCAACUCUCUGGUCAGUAAGUGAUAAAAUGCCAUUUCUAUGCACCCACCUGGCCUGUGUGACUGGGAGAAUCUCUCUUUUUAUUAAAUGUGCUUCAAGUUUUAACA